ACUUCCUCAUCGCCAGGCUCUGCACAGGAAUCCCACGCUUAGGGUUAUAACAGCAGGUGGGAAAUUCCCUGAGCCUGGGGAGCCCUCCUUUUCUCAGAAGACAGUCUCUGAGUACCAGCUGUGUGCCAGGCCCGGAGAAGCCCUGGAUGCCGUUUCGAACAGGCCUGUUCCUAACCCAGGGGGAGGUGGUGGGCUGGGAGGCAGGCAGGUGUCCCGGGCAUCAGCCAGUGGAUGGAGAGAGGCUGCUGGGACUCCUGCUCUGCCUAUAGGGACAUAAGACCCAGCUUCUGAGGGACAAAAAGGCAGAGAUGGGAGGACAAGGACUCCAAGGUCAGGCGUUCGGAGCGAAAGACCCCUUAAACCAGGGAGCUCGCAUGCCCAGGGAGUGGAUUCCAGCGCUUUGUUGAGACGCCUCCAUGUGCUUCCGGAGAGGAGAUGGGAAGACAGCCUGGCCUUGCAGGCAGGGGCUUCCUGGUGCUGCCACAGACUCAGGGCCAGGUGGUGGGCACAGGCAGCCACAGGUGCCAGGACCGCAGUCCUGCAGAGCAAGGAGGAGAAAGCAAAGUCCGAGGCUGGGCGAGGGCAGCCAGGGCAUCCUGCACUGCCCCUGAAGGUGCCCAGAGCUCUCCAGGCGUGACCAGGGUCCCAGGACAUGGGAACAGGGAGGGUGAAGGCCCCAGGCUGCACAGGGCAUUUGAUCAGUGAGGCUGUGUUCUGCGUCCGCAGUUCCACUCACGCUUCCUCCUUUGGAAAGCAAGUCUCAUGGGCUGCACCCUGCUCCCACUCCUGGGCGAACAGCUUCCCCGGAGGGUCUCUUGGGUGCCUCUUGGCGUCAGAUGUCUCCUGAUUCACCAUUCCCGGCCCCCACAGGUCCUGGUCCCUGCCCCUCAGAGGUGGUUGGGGGGUGGGAAGGAUUUGGCCACAAACUGAUCAAUCAGAUUACAGUUGGAGCAGGUGUGCAGAUGGAAGGUGGGGUGCCGGGGCACUUCACAGCCAGGGGCUGUCGCCUCUGCAAGCCUUGCUGGCCCGGGGCUGAUCCGGCUGAGGCCCUGCACUCUGAGCAUCCCCAGGGAGCCUUCCCUGACUGUGGGAUUCCCUCCCCGGCCAGAGCUAGGGGACCCUCUCUAUGCCUCAUAGAACCUCCCUCACGGAACCAUCACUAUUCUGUCGAAAUUCCCAACUUAGCAGGCCUGGGUCUCCCUCCCUCUGUGUGGGAGGUGGGUGGUUGUUGAAACCAAGGACUUUAGACCGUGGGCUCCUCCCGCCCCUGCUCUGCUGAUGGAGCCCAAGGUAUGAGGUGAGCUGGGGCCUGGGAGGCCAGUUCUCAGGGUGACAGCCACAGCCAUGGGGGCAGGGGUGAUGGCUGGGCUUACAUGACACCCACUCGUCCCUGUCUGCAGCCAACUUGCCCCCCAUGAGGGUUUCCUCAUCCUGUACUAAACAUUACACAGGAGCUGCCUCUUGGGGAGCAGCCUCUGUGAAGGGACCUGUCGCCACAGUGGUGGCCCGAGCCGAGAGCAGUGCGGGGAGGGAGGAGGUGCUCGUGGGUGGGAAAAGGCAUGGCAGGGAUGGCAGCUUCAGUGUGCACUUCUGCUUUGGUCUGACAGGUGUGCGGGUGCGUGUGUGUGUGUGUGUGUGUGCUUGCACACAGGCUUGAGAAUUGCCUAGCCCCUCAGAGCCUCAGUUUCCCCAUCUCUGCACUGGGGAGGUAGGCCUUCCCUGGGGGUUGCUGGACCAAGGUGUCUGGUACCAGGAGGUGUGCCAGUUGGCACCUACUGUCCUGGGACUGUCCUGAGGUCAGUCUUGACCGCCUCUGGGUUUUCAGGCUCAGAGCCUCGGGGGAGGGCUGGGGGUGCUGGGGAAGGAAACUGGGCUCCAUCUGUGCUUGAUGUAUGGUGAGAUUUUCCGUGCUGCUGUCUAACGCAGGCCCAGCUUGCCCUGUUUGGUAAAAAACUGAGGUGGGGAAGAAAUAAGCCCAGCAUCUCCGCAACUCCUACCUCCCAUCUCCCCGCCCCUGCAAGACAUUCUGAGCAGACACUGGGACAGACUUUGUGGCGCAUGGACUCGUCCCCCUGCUCCUGGCUUGAAGCUCCCAGGGGUGCCUCUCUGCCCUUCCCAGGUGCUCGAUGUCCAGGGCCUCCUGCCUCCCCUUCACAGCUGCGUCCUCUGUCCCUGACUGCAGACCCCACGCACCCCCAACAGCUGCCUGAUUUGCCUCCCAGUCCCCUGCCACGUUCCCCGCCCAGAGAGCAGGGUGGAAGUGGGAGAUGGGGAUAAGGACAGGAGGCUCUGGGGGUUGUCCUGGCAGCUGGAAGGCCCCAGCCUCGUGGGCCCAUCAGGGCUCUGAGGCCCGGACGGAGGCCCUGGCAAGCCCUGGGUGCCCUGCCCCCCAGCAUCCACCACAAAAGGGGUGACAGGACAGCAGGAGGCCAGACUUGCACUUUUGCUCCCAGACAGAGGUCAGAGGCAUGGCCGUCCCGGUUCUCCAUGCCCUGCCUGCAGAGGGGAUGUUUGCUGGCCACUGAGGGGCUUCAAGCCAGGAGCAAGGGGACGAGUCCACGCACCGGAAAGUCUGUCCCAGUGUUUGCUCAGAAUAUCUUGCUGGGCGGGGAGAUGGGAGGCAGGAGCUGCGGGGCACGCUGGGCUUAUUUCUUCCCCACCUCACAUUUCACCAAGCAGGGGCAGCAGAGCCUGUAUUAGACAGCAGCAGGGAAAAUCUUCUCACCACACAUCAGGCACGGAUGGAACCCCUUUUCCUUCCUCUGCAUCCCCAUUGCUCCCCGAGGCUCUGGACUUGAAAACUGCCCUGGCCAUGGUGUUCUGGAGGGGCAGGGUGGACCUUUCCCCACCCACAAUCAGUGAACAGUGAGGCCCCCCAUGACCAAGCCCUCCCUUUGGGGACAGCAGGGUUCUGACUAUGUGCUUGCCAUCCUCCUCUCUUAUUAGCGCCUCUGUCUGAGGCCGGAGCUGAGGAGGACGUGGCUGACCCCGUCCCUGCGGCCACAGCUGGGGUUUGUCCCCUGUGCACCUCAGCCCUGGCCCAGGCUGCCGUCCCCAUGGCCCCUGUGCCUAUUUGUGACGCUGGAAGGGGGACUCGAAUGUGUCCUUCUGUGUCUUCUGACAGGCGACGGAGCACUGUUCCGGGAGCACGGUCUGUUGGGUGUGACGGCCCAGCAAAGAGGCAGUGACCGGCUCCUGAGGAGGGGCACAAGGCACCCAGGGGUUCUGCCUCGACAGGGAAGGGGACUCCAGGCAGAAAACCAGCGAGAGGAGGCCCCGUGGAGGAAGGGAGCACAGCAAACCCGAGAUAGGGAGGGGAGGCGCAGCAGCGGUGCGGGAUCACGCCCACCACAACACGGUGCACGGUGCGGUGAGGGGCUCGCUGGAUCUGAAAGGGCCAGGCAUGUGAGGUCUCUGCGGGUCAUGGAGAACCUCCCUGCCGUGACCACUGAGGAGCCGACCCCCAUGGGGAGGGGUCCUGUGGGACCCUCAGGAGGUGGCAGCACCCGGGACCAGGUCCGGACUGUGGUCAUGAGGCCCUCUGUGAGCUGGGAGAAAGCGGGGCCCGAGGAGGCCAAGGCGCCAGUGAGAGGCGACGAGGCUCCUCCUGCCCGCGUGGCUGGGCCUGCUGCUGGGACCCCUCCCUGCCAGAUGGGGGUUUAUCCCACAGACCUGACCCUGCAGCUGCUGGCUGUGCGGAGGAAGAGCAGACUGCGGGACCCCGGCCUACAGCAGACCCUCCGGGGCCAGCUCCGCCUGCUGGAGAAUGAUAGCCGGGAGAUGGCCCGCGUGCUUGGGGAAUUAUCAGCCAGGCUGCUGUCCAUCCACAGUGACCAGGACCGGAUCGUGGUGACGUUUAAGACUUUUGAAGAAAUCUGGAAGUUUUCCACCUACCAUGCUCUCGGCUUCACUCAUCACUGCCUGGCAAACCUGCUCAUGGACCAGGCCUUCUGGCUGCUCUUGCCCAGUGAGGAGGAGGAGACGGCCAUCCAAGUCCAUGUGGAUGAGAACGCCUUAAGGCUGACCCACGAGAGCCUCCUCAUCCAAGAAGGGCCCUUCUUUGUCCUGUGUCCUGACCACCAUGUGAGAGUGAUGACGGGUCCCCGGGAUGCAGGAAAUGGCCCCCAGGCCCUCAGGCAGGCUUCGGGGGCACCCCAGGGAGAGGCGGCCCCGGAAACAGACUCUUCACCGCCGAGCCCCAGCGUGUCCUCCGAGGAGGUGGCAGUGGCGGCCGCCCCGGAGCCUUUGAUUCCAUUUCAUCAGUGGGCUCUUAGGAUCCCCCAGGACCCCAUCGACGAUGCCAUGGGUGGCCCUGUGAUGCCCGGCAACCCGCUGAUGGCUGUGGGCCUGGCCUCGGCAUUGGCAGACUUCCAGGGCUCGGGGCCCGAAGAGAUGACCUUCCGAGGUGGCGACCUCAUCGAGAUCCUUGGGGCGCAGGUGCCCAGCCUGCCCUGGUGCGUGGGCCGACACGCAGCCUCGGGCCGGGUGGGGUUUGUGCGGAGCAGCCUCAUCAGCAUGCAGGGCCCCGUGUCCGAGUUGGAAAGUGCGAUUUUUCUCAAUGAGGAAGAAAAGUCAUUCUUCAGCGAGGGCUGCUUUUCUGAGGAGGAUGCCAGGCAGUUGCUGAGGCGGAUGUCGGGCACCGAUGUCUGCAGCGUGUACAGCCUGGACUCAGUAGAGGAAGCUGAGACCGAGCAGCCGCAGGAAAAAGAAAUACCUCCACCUUGCCUGAGCCUGGAGCCACAGGAGACCUUGCAGAAGGUGAAGAAUGUUCUGGAACAAUGCAAGACCUGCCCAGGCUGCCCCCAGGAGCCAGCGUCCUGGGGUCUCUGUGCGGCAUCCAGCGACGUGAGCUUGCAGGACCCCGAGGAGCCCUCCUUCUGCUUGGAAGCCGAGGACGACUGGGAGGACCCAGAGGCCCUGAGCUCACUGCUGCUGUUCCUGAACGCCCCUGGGUACAAGGCCAGCUUCCGUGGCCUGUACGAUGUGGCGCUGCCGUGGCUGAGCAGCGUGUUCCGCAGCUUCAGCGACGAGGAGGAGCUGACUGGGCGCCUGGCACAGGCCCGGGGGGCGGCCAAGAAAGCUGGCCUCCUCAUGGCCCUGGCCAGGCUCUGCUUCCUCCUGGGGCGGCUGUGCAGCAGGAGGCUCAAGCUGUCCCAGGCCCGGGUGUACUUUGAGGAAGCGCUGGGGGCCCUGGAGGGCAGCUUCGGGGACCUGUUCCUAGUGGUGGCUGUGUACGCCAACCUGGCCAGCAUUUACCGGAAGCAGAAGAACCGGGAGAAGUGUGCACAGGUGGUGCCCAAAGCCAUGGCCCUGCUCCUGGGGACGCCUGACCACAUCUGCAGCACCGAGGCGGAGGGGGAGCUCCUGCAGCUGGCGCUGCGGCGGGCGGUGGGUGGCCAGAGCCUGCAGGCCGAGGCCCGGGCCUGCUUCCUGCUGGCCAGGCACCACGUGCACCUCAAGCAGCCCGAGGAGGCCCUGCCCUUCCUAGAGCGGCUGCUGCUUUUGCACAGGGACUCGGGAGCCCCAGAGGCCGCGUGGCUCUCAGACUGCUACCUACUCCUGGCUGACAUCUACAGCCGCAAGUGCCUGCCCCACCUGGUGCUGAGCUGUGUCAAGGUGGCCUCAUUGCGGACACGGGGCUCGCUGGCCGGCUCGCUGAGGAGUGUGAACCUGGUGCUCCAGAACGCCCCCCAGCCCCACAGCCUCCCUGCCCAAACUUCCCACUACCUCAGGCAAGCGCUGGCCUCCCUGACCCCGGGCACAGGCCAGGCGCUGCGCGGCCCCCUCUACACCAGCUUGGCCCAGCUGUACAGCCACCAUGGCUGCCACGGCCCGGCCAUCACCUUCAUGACGCAGGCAGUGGAAGCCAGUGCUAUUGCCGGAGUCCGUGCCAUCGUGGACCACCUGGUGGCCCUGGCCUGGCUGCACGUGCUUCAUGGGCAGAGCCCGGUGGCCCUGGACAUCCUGCAGUCUGUCCGGGAUGCAGUGGUGGCCAGCGAGGACCAGGAGGGCGUGAUUGCCAACAUGGUGGCCGUGGCUCUGAAGAGGACGGGCCGGACGAGGCAGGCAGCUGAGAGCUACUACCGCGCCCUGCGGGUGGCUCGGGACCUGGGCCAGCAAAGGAACCAGGCAGUGGGGCUGGCCAACUUCGGGGCCCUGUGCCUGCAUGCGGGUGCCAGCAGGCUGGCCCAGCACUACCUCCUGGAGGCCGUGCGGCUGUUCUCGAGGCUGCCCCUUGGGGAGUGUGGCCGGGACUUCACCCACGUGCUCCUGCAGCUGGGCCAUCUCUGCACCCGCCAGGGCCCGGCCCAGCAGGGCAAGGGCUACUACGAGUGGGCCCUUCUGGUCGCCGUGGAGAUGGGCCACGUGGAGAGCCAGCUGCGGGCCGUCCAGCGGCUGUGCCACUUCUACAGCGCCGUCAUGCCCAGCGAGGCCCAGUGUGUCAUCUACCAUGAGCUCCAGCUCUCCCUGGCCUGCAAGGUGGCCGACAAGGUGCUGGAGGGGCAGCUCCUGGAGACCAUCAGCCAGCUCUACCUGUCCCUGGGCACCGAGCGGGCCUACAAAUCCGCACUGGACUACACCAAACGAAGUCUGGGGAUUUUCAUUGACCUCCAGAAGAAAGAGAAGGAGGCGCAUGCCUGGCUGCAAGCAGGGAAGAUCUAUUACAUCUUGCGGCAGAGCGAGCUGGUGGACCUCUACAUCCAGGUGGCACAGAACGUGGCCCUGUACACAGGCGACCCCAACCUGGGGCUGGAGCUGUUUGAGGCGGCUGGAGACAUCUUCUUCGACGGGGCCUGGGAGCGGGAGAAAGCUGUGUCCUUCUACCGGGACCGGGCCCUGCCCCUGGCAGUGACUACGGGCAACCGCAAGGCGGAGCUGCGGCUGUGCAACAAGCUGGUGGCACUGCUGGCCACGCUGGAGGAGCCCCAGGAGGGCUUGGAGUUUGCCCACAUGGCCCUAGCACUCAGCAUCACCCUGGGGGACCGGCUGAACGAGCGCGUGGCCUACCACCGGCUGGCCGCCCUGCAACACCGACUGGGCCAUGGCGAGCUGGCAGAGCACUUCUACCUCAAGGCCCUGUCGCUCUGCAACUCGCCGCUGGAGUUUGACGAGGAGACCCUCUACUACGUGAAGGUGUACCUGGUGCUCGGUGACAUCAUCUUCUACGACCUGAAGGACCCGUUUGAUGCAGCCGGGUACUACCAGCUGGCGCUGGCAGCCGCCGUGGACCUGGGCAACAAGAAGGCACAGCUGAAGAUCUACACGCGGCUGGCCACCAUCUACCACAACUUCCUCCUGGACCGUGAGAAGUCGCUCUUCUUCUACCAGAAGGCCAGGACCUUCGCCACAGAGCUCAACGUCCGCAGGGUCAACCUGCCUCCUCUGCCACUCUGCGGGUGGGCCCCCUGGUUGGCCCCCAGCCACCCUCGCUGAGGACAGCAUCCAAGGGAGUGGGUUUUGUGCAAGGGCUGGGGGUCUCCUGCCUCUCCUGGUGUCGCCGGUGGCUCAUUUUCUGGCAAAUGGAGGCACGAACGCAGGGGCCAAAUAGCAAUAAAUGGGUUUUGUUUUUUUUUUGCAAUAA